AGGCGCAGGCGCAGGCGCAGUGGGGGUGAGGGCGCGUGGGGGCGCACAGGUAAGGCCGGGGUGGGGGUGGGUCGCGACGGGGGCUCUGGGCAGCCUGGGAACUGCCAUUGGGAUUAGUCCGCUCCACUCACUGUCAGCAUUAAGUGGGGGUGCCCAAGACGGGGUGGAUGGGGGGCGCCCUCCAGACCUCUGACCACGGCCUCACCGCCACUCGACCCAACUAUGAAGAGCGCCCCCAGCUGCACGCCAGGACACGACCUUUCCUUCCCCUAGAAACCAGUAAAGGCCGCUGCCCUAUUCAAGAUGAAAUGUGUGGACCGCCCCCAGCCCAGUUGAAAUUUCCCGUGAAAGUCUCUCGCCCCUUCCCCACAGCUCCACUUCAGUGGACUGGAGGGCGCAGGCCUUUGUUCUGACUGCUUCUGUCUGCCUGCCUCCCACCCGACGACACUCACAUGGUAGCGCUGAGCUUCAACACCCUGUAUCAUAGAAGGACGGGGUUUGGCUCCACACCUGCCACUGCUAUUGAAAUAGUUUAGUCUUGCCCCAGUUCACUGAUGAGGAAACUGAGGCCCUAACGGCAGGUGGAGCCGGGUCCCCGACCCCCGAGAUCGGCAGGGCGCUGAAGACGUCCCUUCCACCCUCCAGCCUCUGGUGCACAUGGCUUCCUCCCCGGCGGUGGACGUGUCCUGCAGGCGGCGGGAGAAGCGGCGGCAGCUGGACGCGCGCCGCAGCAAGUGCCGCAUCCGCCUGGGCGGCCACAUGGAGCAGUGGUGCCUCCUCAAGGAGCGGCUGGGCUUCUCCCUGCACUCGCAGCUCGCCAAGUUCCUGUUGGACCGGUUAGGGGCCGGGAGAAGGGCUUGGGGGAGGGUACCCAGGCAGCAGCCCCUAGCCUCCUCUCCAGGGCCUGUCCUGCUGCUCUUUUCCACCCUCAGGUUUCUCACUUUACCAGGACGGCCUGUGUGACUUGUGGCCUCCGAGGGUCCUGCUCCCCUCCUCAUGGUCUCAGCGAAUAGCGGCCCUUAGGGCUGGCCCCUUACAUGUGUGAGUGCCCAGGGCUGAGGGUGGCUGGCCACCUGAGUCCUGACCUGCCUCUUCUCCUGCUGGCAGGUACACUUCUUCAGGCUGUGUCCUCUGUGCAGGUAGGUAGGGGAUGGCAGGGGGUGAGAGCCAGAGGGAAGAGGGACCACAGGGUGACCCAGAAACACCCUCCUUUCAAAGGGAGCCCUGACCGAGAGUGCAGCCUGGUGCCCGGGCUUCGGGGGCCUGGCGGCCAAGAUGGGGGGCUUGUGUGGGAGUGCUCAGCAGGCCAUACCUUCUCCUGGGGACCCUCUUUGAGCCCUACACCUUCAGAGGCACCCAAGCCAGCCUCCCUUCCACAUACUACUCGGAGAAGUUGGUGUUCCGAGGCCACGAGUGGGCAGGAGCUUGCAGAUUUGGAAUCUGAGCAUGAUGAGAGGACUCAAGAGGCCAGGUUGCCCAGGAGGGUGGGACCCCCACCAGAGACCUUCCCACCUCCAGGAGAGGAAGAGGGUGAGGAAGAAGAGGACAAUGAUGAGGAUGAAGAGGAGAUGCUCAGUGAUGCCAGCUUAUGGACCUACAGCUCCUCCCCAGAUGAUAGUGAGCCUGAUGCCCCCAGACUACUGCCUUCCCCUGUCACCUGCACACCUAAAGAGGGGGAGACACCACCAGCCCCUGCAGCACUCUCCAGUCCUCUUGCUGUGCCGGCCUUGUCAGCAUCCUCAUUGAGUUCCAGAGCUCCUCCACCUGCAGAAGUCAGGGUGCAGCCACAGCUCAGCAGGACCCCUCAAGCGGCCCAGCAGACUGAGGCCCUGGCCAGCACUGGGAGUCAGGCCCAGUCUGCUCCAACCCCGGCCUGGGAUGAGGACACUGCACAAAUUGGCCCCAAGAGAAUUAGGAAAGCUGCCAAAAGAGAGCUGAUGCCUUGUGACUUCCCUGGCUGUGGAAGGAUCUUCUCCAACCGGCAGUAUUUGAAUCACCACAAAAAGUACCAGCACAUCCACCAGAAGUCUUUCUCCUGCCCAGAGCCAGCCUGUGGGAAGUCUUUCAACUUUAAGAAACACCUGAAGGAGCACAUGAAGCUGCACAGUGACACCCGGGACUACAUCUGUGAGUUCUGCGCCCGGUCUUUCCGCACUAGCAGCAACCUUGUCAUCCACAGACGUAUCCACACUGGAGAAAAACCCCUGCAGUGUGAGAUAUGCGGGUUUACCUGCCGCCAGAAGGCUUCCCUGAACUGGCACCAGCGCAAGCAUGCAGAGACGGUGGCUGCCUUGCGCUUCCCCUGUGAAUUCUGCGGCAAGCGCUUUGAGAAGCCAGACAGUGUUGCAGCCCACCGUAGCAAAAGUCACCCAGCCCUGCUUCUAGCCCCUCAAGAGUCACCCAGUGGUCCCCUAGAGCCCUGUCCCAGCAUCUCUGCCCCUGGGCCUCUGGGAUCCAGCGAGGGGUCCAGGCCCUCUGCAUCUCCUCAGGCUCCAACCCUGCUUCCUCAGCAAUGAGCUCUCCUCCAGCUUUGGCUUUGGGAAGCCAGACUCCAGGGACUGAAAAGGAGCAACAAGGAGAGGGUCUGCUUGAGAAAUGCCAGAUGCUUGGUCCCCAGGAACUAAGGCGACAGAGUGCAGGGUGGGGGCAAGACUGGGCUGUAGGGGAGCUGGACUACUUUAGUCUUCCUAAAGGACAAAAUAAACAGUAUUUUAUGCA